AGCCUUCUCACUCCUCACUGAGUCCACUCUGAACGUGCUAAAAUGGGAAGGAGGCGGUGUUUUGCUGAUCUGUUAAAUUCUUAGUGAAGUUUCCUUGAUUUCCAGUGGCUGCUGUUGUUUGAGUUUGGUUUGGAGCAAAACUGAGGUAGUCCUAACAUUUCUGGGACUGAAUCCAGGCAAGAGAAAGAAGAAAAAGAAGAAGAAAAAGAGGAGGAAAAAGGUAGGGAGAAAUAAAGGGAGGAGAGAAGCACAGUGAAAGAAAAAAAAAGUCCCUUUUCGACAUCACAUUCCUGUGUUUUCCCUCAGCCUGGAAAACAUAUUAAUCCCAGUGCUUUUACGCCCGGAAACAAAGAGACUAAGCCAGACUAUGGGGGAAAGGGAGAUAAGAAGGAUCCUGGAACUUUAAAGAGGGAAAGAGUGAGAUUCAGAAAUCGCCAGGACUGGACUUUAAGGGACGUCCUGUGUCAGCACAAGGGACUGGCACACACAGACACACGAGACCGAGGAGAAACUGCAGACAAAUGGAGAUACAAAGACUUAGAAGGACAGCUCCUUUCACCUCAUCCUACUUGUCCAGAAGGUAAAAAGACACAGCCAGAAAGAAAAGGCAUCGGCUCAGCUCUCAGAUCAGGACAGGCUGUGGAUCUGUGGCGGUACUCUGAAAGCUGGAGCUGCAGCACACCCCUUUUGUAUUGCUCACCCUCGGUAAAGAGAGAGAGGGCUGGGAGGAAAAGUAGUUCAUCUAGGAAACUGUCCUGGGAACCAAACUUCUGAUUUCUUUUGCAACCCUCUGCAUUCCAUCUCUAUGAGCCACCAUUGGAUUACACAAUGACAUGGAGAAUGGGACCCCGUUUCACUAUGCUGUUGGCCAUGUGGCUAGUGUGUGGAUCAGAACCCCACCCCCAUGCCACUAUUAGAGGCAGCCACGGAGGACGGAAAGUGCCUUUGGUUUCUCCGGACAGCAGUAGGCCAGCUCGGUUUCUGAGGCACACUGGGAGGUCUCGCGGAAUUGAGAGAUCCACUCUGGAGGAACCAAACCUUCAGCCUCUCCAGAGAAGGAGGAGUGUGCCCGUGUUGAGACUAGCUCGCCCAACAGAGCCGCCAGCCCGCUCGGACAUCAAUGGGGCCGCCGUGAGACCUGAGCAAAGACCAGCAGCCAGGGGCUCUCCGCGUGAGAUGAUCAGAGAUGAGGGGUCCUCAGCUCGGUCAAGAAUGUUGCGUUUCCCUUCGGGGUCCAGCUCUCCCAACAUCCUUGCCAGCUUUGCAGGGAAGAACAGAGUAUGGGUCAUCUCAGCCCCUCAUGCCUCGGAAGGCUACUACCGCCUCAUGAUGAGCCUGCUGAAGGACGAUGUGUACUGUGAGCUGGCGGAGAGGCACAUCCAACAGAUUGUGCUCUUCCACCAGGCAGGUGAGGAAGGAGGCAAGGUGAGAAGGAUCACCAGCGAGGGCCAGAUCCUGGAGCAGCCCCUGGACCCUAGCCUCAUCCCUAAGCUGAUGAGCUUCCUGAAGCUGGAGAAGGGCAAGUUUGGCAUGGUGCUGCUGAAGAAGACGCUGCAGGUGGAGGAGCGCUAUCCAUAUCCCGUUAGGCUGGAAGCCAUGUACGAGGUCAUCGACCAAGGCCCCAUCCGUAGGAUCGAGAAGAUCAGGCAGAAGGGCUUUGUCCAGAAAUGUAAGGCCUCUGGUGUAGAGGGCCAGGUGGUGGCGGAGGGGAAUGACGGUGGAGGGGGAGCAGGAAGGCCAAGCCUGGGCAGCGAGAAGAAGAAAGAGGACCCAAGGAGAGCACAAGUCCCACCAACCAGAGAGAGUCGGGUGAAGGUCCUGAGAAAACUGGCCGCCACUGCACCAGCUUUGCCCCAACCUCCCUCAACCCCCAGAGCCACCACCCUUCCUCCUGCCCCAGCCACAACAGUGACUCGGUCCACGUCCCGGGCGGUAACAGUUGCUGCAAGACCUAUGACCACCACUGCCUUUCCCACCACGCAGAGGCCCUGGACCCCCUCACCCUCCCACAGGCCCCCUACAACCACUGAGGUGAUCACUGCCAGGAGACCCUCAGUUUCAGAGAAUCUUUACCCUCCAUCCCGGAAGGAUCAGCACAGGGAGAGGCCACAGACAACCAGGAGGCCCAGCAAGGCCACCAGCUUGGAGAGCUUCACAAAUGCCCCUCCCACCACCAUCUCAGAACCCAGCACAAGGGCUGCUGGCCCAGGCCGUUUCCGGGACAACCGCAUGGACAGGCGGGAACAUGGCCACCGAGACCCAAAUGUGGUGCCAGGUCCUCCCAAGCCAGCAAAGGAGAAACCUCCCAAAAAGAAGGCCCAGGACAAAAUUCUUAGUAAUGAGUAUGAGGAGAAGUAUGACCUCAGCCGGCCUACUGCCUCUCAGCUGGAGGACGAGCUGCAGGUGGGGAAUGUUCCCCUUAAAAAAGCAAAGGAGUCUAAAAAGCAUGAAAAGCUUGAGAAACCAGAGAAGGAGAAGAAAAAAAAGAUGAAGAAUGAGAACGCAGACAAGUUACUUAAGAGUGAAAAGCAAAUGAAGAAGUCUGAGAAAAAGAGCAAGCAAGAGAAAGAGAAGAGCAAGAAGAAAAAAGGAGGUAAAACAGAACAGGAUGGCUAUCAGAAACCCACCAACAAACACUUCACGCAGAGUCCCAAGAAGUCAGUGGCCGACCUGCUGGGGUCCUUUGAAGGCAAACGAAGACUCCUUCUGAUCACUGCUCCCAAGGCUGAGAACAAUAUGUAUGUGCAACAACGUGAUGAAUAUCUGGAAAGUUUCUGCAAGAUGGCUACCAGGAAAAUCUCUGUGAUCACCAUCUUCGGCCCUGUCAACAACAGCACCAUGAAAAUCGACCACUUUCAGCUAGAUAAUGAGAAGCCCAUGCGAGUGGUGGAUGAUGAAGACUUGGUAGACCAGCGUCUCAUCAGCGAGCUGAGGAAAGAGUACGGAAUGACCUACAAUGACUUCUUCAUGGUGCUAACAGAUGUGGAUCUGAGAGUCAAGCAAUACUAUGAGGUACCAAUAACAAUGAAGUCUGUGUUUGAUCUGAUCGAUACUUUCCAGUCCCGAAUCAAAGAUAUGGAGAAGCAGAAGAAGGAGGGCAUUGUUUGCAAAGAGGACAAAAAGCAGUCCCUGGAGAACUUCCUAUCCAGGUUCCGGUGGAGGAGGAGGUUGCUGGUGAUCUCUGCUCCUAACGAUGAAGACUGGGCCUAUUCACAGCAGCUCUCUGCCCUCAGUGGUCAGGCGUGCAAUUUUGGUCUGCGCCACAUAACCAUUCUGAAGCUUUUAGGCGUUGGAGAGGAAGUUGGGGGAGUGUUAGAACUGUUCCCAAUUAAUGGGAGCUCUGUUGUUGAGCGAGAAGACGUACCAGCCCAUUUGGUGAAAGACAUUCGUAACUAUUUUCAAGUGAGCCCGGAGUACUUCUCCAUGCUUCUAGUCGGAAAAGACGGAAAUGUCAAAUCCUGGUAUCCUUCCCCAAUGUGGUCCAUGGUGAUUGUGUACGAUUUAAUUGAUUCGAUGCAACUUCGGAGACAGGAAAUGGCGAUUCAGCAGUCACUGGGGAUGCGCUGCCCAGAAGAUGAGUAUGCAGGCUAUGGUUACCAUAGUUACCACCAAGGAUACCAGGAUGGUUACCAGGAUGACUACCGUCAUCAUGAGAGUUAUCACCAUGGAUACCCUUACUGAGCAGAAAUAUGUAACCUUAGACUCAGCCAGUUUCCUCUGCAGCUGCUAAAACUACAUGUGGCCAGCUCCAUUCUUCCACACUGCGUACUACAUUUCCUGCCUUUUUCUUUCAGUGUUUUUCUAAGACUAAAUAAAUAGCAAACUUUCACCUAUUCAUGAGUUAUUAUUGAAACCUCAAAUCAUAAAGACAUUUAAAAGAAUUGUUUUUCUAACUGGAGGGGCUCUAGUGCUAAAUAAUAGUACUGAAAAUUGAUAUUAUUUUCCUUUUCUUAUAUGAAGGACCUUAUUUGGCAUAUAAAAUUUUAUAAAAUAUGUAUUUAAAGCUUUUUCUUAUUUUUUGUAUUAAUUGGUAAGUGAAAACUCUGUUAAAGAUCACACCACAAUGUUUUCAAGAAACAUCUGAAAAGAUAAAACAAAGAACAAAUAACUUAUAAUACUUACUUAAAUUGACACUUUUUGAAAUGCCAGUCUGAAAAUAAUUAAGAUAUCUCUGCUUUGUAUGAGUUUCUUUUAUGAAACUUGAUACCACGGGAGUCCAGUAAUAUUGGCCACAAAAGCCAGAGAAAGUACCAAGCCCAGCUUUGUUAUCAUAGCCACUUCCUGCCCUGCUUCUGUUAUUUUUAGUGUUUUUUCAGAUAUAAAUCGGGGUCCAGGAAAUCCUCACCAGAAUCUGGCACUGCAGCCAAAGGCGAUACUUCCAGAGUUCUAGUAGGCUGCUAUGGAAUUUCUGGCAUGAAAAUUCUUGACCCCUCACACUUUACCCCCUGUACAGCACAGGCAUACCAUGGAGAUAUUACAGGAUCAGUUCCAGACCACCAUAAUAAAGUGGAUAUCGCAAUAAAGUGAGUCACACAAAAUUUUUGGUUUCUCAGUGCAUAUAAAAGUUAUGUUUACACUCUUUAGUAGUCUAUUAAGUGUAUAAUAGCUUUAUGUCCAAAAAAUGUACAUGUUUUAUUUUAAAAAUACUUUAUUGCUAAAAAUUGCUAAUGAUCAUAAUCUUUUUGCAUUGAUGUUGAUGGCUGCUGAAUGAUCAGGGUGGUGGUUACUGAAGGUUGGGGGUGAUGGUGGCAAUUUCUUAAAAUAAGACAGCAAUGAAGUUUGCCACUUCGAUUGACUUUUUCUUCAUGAAAGAUUUCUCUGCAGCAUGUGAUGCUGUAUGAUAGCAUUUUACCAGUAGUACAACUUCUUUUGAAAUUGGAGCCAAUCCUCUCAAACCCUGUUGCUGCUUUAUUAAUGAAAUUUAUGUAAUGUUGUAAAUCCUUUGUUGUCAUUUCAAUAAUGUACAUAGCAACUUACGCGAGUAGAUUCCAUCUCAAGAAAUCACUUUCUUCGUUCAUUCAUAAGAAGCAAGUCUUCAUCUAUUAAACUUUUGUAAUGAGAUUGCAGCAAUUCAGUCACAUCUUCAGGCUCCACUUCUAAUUCCAGUUCUCUUGCUAUUUCCACUAUGUCUAUAGCAGAGCUUCCUCCAAUGAAGUCUUGGGCCUCUUAAAAUCAUCCAUGAGGGAUGGAAUCAGUUUCCGAACUCAUUGAUCUUCCUAUUUUGACCUUCUCCCAUGAAUCACGAUGUUCUUAACAGCAUCUAGAAUGGUGAAUCCUUUCCAGGUUUUUAAUUUGCUUUGCCCAGAUCCAUUAGCGGGAUCACAAUCUGUGACAGUUAUAGUCUUACGAAAAGUGCAAAUGACUCCUUGAUUCCUGUGCUGCACAAUAGGUAUUGUGUUAGCAGGCACGAAAAUAUUAAUCUCCUUGUAUAUCUCUAUCCAAGUUCUUGGGUGACUGGGUAUAUUGUCAGUGAACAGCUAUAUAUAUAUAUAUUAUAGUGGUCUGGAACUGAUCAUUUAUAUAUAUAUUUUAUAUACAUAUAUAAAAUAUAUAAUAUAUAUUAUAUAUAUAUAUAUUUUUUUCGAGAUGGAGUCUCGCUCUGUCACCCAGGCUGGAGUGCAGUGGUGCGAUCUUGGCUCACUGCAACCUCUGCCUCCGGGGUUCAAGUGAUUCUCCUGCCUCAGACCCCUGAGUAGCUGGAUUUACAGGCGCCCACCACUACACCCAGCUUAUUUUUGUAUUUUUAGUAGAGAUGGGGUUUCACCAUGUUAGUCAGGGUGGUCUCGAACUACUGACUUUGGCCUCGGCCUCCCAAAGUGCUGGGAUUACAGGCAUGAGCCACUGCGCCCGGCCCGAACAGCAAUAUUUUUAAAAGAUUCUUUUUUUUUCUGAGCAGUAAGACUCAAAAAGUGAGCUUAAAAUGUCCAGUAAACCAUGCUGUCCAUAGACAUGCUGUCAUUCAGGCUUUGUUGCUCCAUUUAUAGAGCACAGGCAGAUUAGAUUUAGCAUAAUUCUGAAAAGUCGUAGGAUUUGGGGAAAUGGUAAAUGAGCAUUGAUUUCAACUUAAAAUCACCAGCUGCGUUAACUUCUAACAAGGAGUAAGCCUGUUGGUUGAAGCUUUGAAGUGAGGCAUUGACUACUCCUCUCUAGAUACGUAAGUCUGAGAUGGCAUCUUCUUCCAAUAUAAGGCUGUUUCAUCUCUUUUGAAAAUCUAUUGUUUAGUGUAGCCACUUUCAUUAAUUAUCUUAACUAGAUCUUCUGGAUAACUUACUGCAGCUUCUACAUCAACAUUUGCUGCUUUACUUUGCACUUUUAUGGAUGCACAAGGCUUCUUUUCUUCAAACUCAUGAACCAGACUCUGCUACCUUCAAACUUUUUUUCUGAAGCUUCCUCACCUCCCUUUAGCUUUCAUAGAAUUGAAGAGAGUUAGGGCCUUGCUCUGAACUAGGCUUUGGCUUAAGGGAAUUUUGUGGCUGGCUUGAUCUUCUAUUCAGAUGACUCAAAGUUUCUCCAUAUCAGCAGUAAGGCUGUUUUACUUUUUUAUCAUUCAUGCAUUCACAAAGUAGCACUUUUAAUUUCCUUCAAGAACUUUUCCUUUGCAUUUACAACUUGGUUGUUUGGCAUAAGAGGCUUAGCUUUCAGCCUGUCUCAGCUUUUGACACACCUUCCUCACUAAGCUUAUUCAUUUCUAGCUUUUGAUUUAAAGUGAAAGAUUGCAACUUCCUCUCACUUGAAAUACCUGGAGGCUAUUUUAGGGUUAUUAAUUGAUCUACUUUCAAUAUUGUGUCUCAGGGACUAAGGAGGCCUGAGAAGAAGGAGAAAGAUUGGAGAAAGGUUGGUUGUUGGAGCAAUCAGAACAUACACACAUUUAUUAAGUUUACUGUGUUAUAUAAGUGUGGUUCAUGGUGCCCCCAGUAAUUAUAAUAGCAACAUCAAAGAUCGUUGACUACAGAUUUUAAUAACAGAGAUAAUAAUGAAACAGUGUGAAAUAUGGCAAGAAUUACCAAAAUGUGACACAGAGACAUAAAGUGAGUACAUACUAUUGCAAAAAUGAUGUCAACAGACUUCCUUGAUGCAGGGUUGCCACAAACCUUCAAUUUGUAAAAAAUGCAGUAUCUGAGAAGUAUAAUAAAAUAAGAUGUGCCUGUACUUACUUGCUAAUGGACCUAUUACCAUACUGGCAUCUUAUAAAAAAAAUUACAAGGAAGGAGAUUAUAUCCAGGGAUUCUUUUUGUUUUCAAGGCAAAGGUUACCAAGUUACAAUGGACCAAAGUAGCUGGAAUGCAAAGGAGUAUAAUCCUUGUCUUUGAAAAAAGAGCAUUUGUUUCAAUCAUAUGGCAUAUCAAAGUAAACUUUCUCCCUUCCUCCCUCCUUUCGUUGCUGCUGCUUCUUUUUUUUCUCUUUUUUUUUUUCUUUUUUUGGAGAGGGUCUCACUCUGUCACCCAGGCUGCAGUGCAGUAGUGCAAUCUUGGCUCACUGCAAACUCAGCUUCCCUCAAACAAUCCUCCCACCUCAGCAUCCCAAGUUAGCUGGGACCACAGCCAUGCUCCACCAUGCCCAGCCAUCCUUGCUUCUUUACUACAUUUCUUUUUUCAACAAAUAUUUAUCAAGUAAUAUUGUCAAGUAAUAUUUAUGAGCUUCCCCUCAGAUAGGCAUUUAGCAUCAUGAUGGCACCAUCCUCUAACAAUAAUGGGAAGGCUAUUUUCCACUGUUAUUAAUCAUUAAUUCUCCAAAUCAUUUUAGUAUUAUUAUUAAUUCUAAUAAGUACAGAGAUUAAUAAAUGCAUUCAAACCACAUGUGAAUAUUUGCUAUAGGUUUAUCUGUGCCUACUGUAUGUUCAGAUUUUUCUUUAUAUCUGAACUUUGUUAUAAAUAAAUGACAGUAAAAAUGGAAUUUAUAGUUCAAUGAACUUGACAAAUCACUUAUUCUGCCAUUCAUUUUCCAUAAAGACCAUUCAUUCUUCCUUGUUUUACAGGUAACUGAGCUCCAGAAAGCUCAAGUGACUUUAGAACUCAGUUCUUAGUGUGUGAAUUAUGCUCCCAUCUCAUCCCUCUUCCUUGAUGGAGCACUUUCCUCCUCAUUUUUUCUUGGAUAGUCUGUACAAGCUGCCUGAGGUGUGCAGGAAAGUGAGCCACGUCGAAGUGUACUGCUUUUAAAUUUUUGCCAGGAUGAAGCAUAGCCCAAAGUUGCCAAUAAAAAUGGAUUUCUUUACCUUUCUGAAAUUGUGUGAUGACAAUUUCUAAGUAAAGGACCCAAAUCAUGUCAACUUCAGGAAAUAUAAUAAUGAGGGAGCCAGGAGCAGUGAGGGGCUCACACCUGUAAUCCCAGCACUUUGGGAGGCCAAGGUGAGCGGGUCGCUUGAGCCCAGGACUUCGAGACCAGCCUGGGCAACACGGCAAAACCCUGUCUCUACAAAAAAAUACAAAAAAUUAGCUGGGUAAGGUGGUGUGUGUCUGUGGUCCCAGCUAUUCAGGAGGCUGAAGUGAGAGAAUCGCUUGAGCCUAGGAGGUCGAGGCUUCAGUGUGCCGUGAUCGUGCCACAGCACUCCAUCAUCAUCAUCCUGGGUGACAAAGUGAGACCCUGUCUCCCCACCAAAAAAAAGAGGGAGUUUCAUCUCCCAAGAAAAUGAAUUAGAUAGGAAUAAUAGAAAAUUUACUCUCAGAAUAAUAGGGUUCUAGCUCCUGCAACCAAAAAAAGAUAGUUCUUUUUUACAACCUGAGAUUACUUUUUCAAGCAUUUCUCCAGUUCCACUGGCAUUGAAAUAAUAGUUAGCAAUGCAUCUGAGCUUUUCUUCCUCUAAUGAGCAGGCAGAGAAGUCAUAGAUCAUCAUUUGGAGGACUAUAAAAUAAGACAUAGCUUAGCAAAAGGACCAAAAUACAUUCAGAGGAGGAUGCUAUUGGUGAAUGUCCUCAAAGCCUAUAAUCUGGAAAAAUACAAGGCAUAUCUCUGAAACUGUGAGGAUUAGCAAACUAGCUAACCUGAAUCUCUGUCUUCUGGUAGUAUAAACUAGGUAGUUUCAAAUCUGAGUAGUUUCUCCAUAAAAGCAUUUCUUCCCAAACGUUUCUUACCAAACUCCCAAAUAAAUGAGAAAAAUAAAAUACAGUUUUAUAAUUUUUGAGAAAGAUUAUGGGAUUAUGGUAUUUAAAAAGAAAAGCAUUCUGUAGAGUUGGGGAAAUCUGGAAGACUCUUGAGGACAUAGCUUUGCCGAAAUUGCUGGUUGUCACAAGACUCUUCAAAAACUACUUUUCAUCAGACAUCUCCCAGGGCUCUGAGGUGAAUAUUAAUUCAGCAGAAAGAUCCUUUUCUGCUACAUAGGCAGGAGGUCCAGACACAGGGGAGUGGGUGCAACCCAGCUGGUCCCAUUUUCUGUAAUAUAAUUAACAAUGAAGCUCAUACUUUCUCAACUUCUAGAAGCCUGGAGGAUGGAAGCAGCCCGAGAGUAGGGUGAAUGAUGGCCUCAGUGGGCCCUUCUUAAUGUGUCUCAGUACUGAAUGUGUGGAGAUUGUAGAAAAAUAGAAGGCCCUUGGAAAAAACCUCUGUUCGUUUCUCUGUUCGUUUCGCUCCCUGAUCUCCCUGCCGGAUUGCUUUUCUUUCCUUUCUCUUCCUUGGCUGUCCUUUACCUCAUGGUGUGGGGUGUGCAGAUAGCAGGUUGUGGCUUGGUGAGUGCUCUUCACUUCAGGUCAAGGUGAGGCACAGUUAACAUGCUAACUACUUUCCUCAGUUCUCUCUGAGUUGUGUAAAGCUCCCGAUGCCAGACUUCCUCUUAAUUUUGCACAUUAUUAAAGUCCAAAGAGUUAAGAUUUGGUGAUGAGGGGCAAAGGGCCAGCUGUCACAGAAAUCAAUGAAAUGAUACACAGAAAUGGGUAUCAUGAAAAGGCCACUGGACUUGGGAAAACUGGGUGCCUGUCCUUGCCCUGCCAUGUACUUACCUGUGUGACUGGAGGUGAGAUGUUUUACCUAUGGGCCUCAGUUUCUCAUUACAAAAUGACAGAGAAGACUAGAUACCUAAGUUCCUAAGUUUGUGACAUUUGUGAAUUUUUCUUGGCCCUCUGUGAGUAGAGUGCUAAAUUUAGAGGCUUCCUGUGGUUGAACUGAUGUCCAAUUCUCAGGGAACCCAGACUUCUCAGUUCAGAACCCAGUUCCAGAUUUUUGUGGGAAUAGGGAAAGGUAUUAAAUAACUCCAUUGAAUUCUUUCCUGCAUAAUGCCCUGCUGUGGCUGAGACUCAAUGAGGUCAUCACCUCCAACACACAGAACCCCUCAUCAUCUCCUUACAGCCAGACUGGAGCUUCCAAGGACAUCAGGUUGGCAAGGAUUGUGAGUACCCUAAACAUCUAAAGAGGCCCUCUAAUAAGGGACAUAUUUGUUCUUCAACAGUUUCCUAACUUGAGACCACAAAUGCGUAAUCUCUCUAAUAUCCUAAAGCUUGGACAAACUGGGCAGCCCCUGAGCAGACCGCACAGAGCUUAAAUGUCAGUGCUUUCCUUCCAGAAAGAAAAAGAAUGGUCCUACACCUCCCAAUCCAUGGGCUGAUACAUAUGCCAAGGGAGCCGGAUGAAGAAGUGGGUGAUUUUAAAUAGCUAAGACUGCCCAUGGGCAAACGUUCUUUGGCUUUUCUCCUCUGCAAUAAGUAUACCUUCCUCUCUCCUGGUCCUUUUCUCCUUUCCCAGGCCCCUCUAUCAAUAAUAAUUCUGGCUCUCAGAUGACUACAGUUGAUUAGGUGGAACUGAUAGGAUAAAGGUGACACCCUUCCCAAGGCUAUCUAUAAUGCAAAAAGAUAUCCAAGAAAAAGAGAGGUAGGGAACACCUUGGGAAACCAUUUCUGGAAGACAGCCAGUCCCUGCUGUAGACAAGCCUCAUUUUCCUUCCCCCAAAUGUUAAAGAGUAAAUUCCUCCUGUAGCCUUAGCUCUCUUUUCUAUCUUUGGCUUGCUUUUUAUGAACUAUCUUUAGAGUGCCAAAUUAGAACAGGGUAGGCAGAGGCAGGAAUAUGCCCAAAUUUGGGAAGACCUGGUUGGGAAUAGUCGAAAGCCUUGAUAUGUGCAAAGAAAGAACCAUUUGAUCAACCCAGUUCUUAAUACAGGAUACUAACUUAAAAUUUAGACUCAAGUUAUACGAUAAUUCAAACAUUUAUUGUAUUUAUACUAUUCUAUAUGUACUUUUCCAGGAACCAGGAAUACAAAACUGACAUUUCUCUGUACAGAGGCUCAGACUAGUAGAGAACAGUUAGGUACGCCGUUAAUUAUAAACUAAUAUGUAUCAUCAAUUAUGGGUUUUUAUGGGGGUUUGGCAGGUGGAAGGGACCAGGGAGAGAUGAUGAGUGAUGAUGGUUAUGUAGUCUUUAGGAGGAUGCAAUUAUAACAUUGCUCUUCCUUUCACGCACCACAUGAUUUAGCAAGUACUUCAUAUUGGCUCCACCAUUAACAUGGUCAAUGGCUUCUGGAUACUCACAGUUCAGGCACAGUUUCUCCUGAAGAUUUUUUACCUCUCCCAUCUUUAAGAAAUUGUCUGGAUGUCCAUGAAAGAUGCUGACACUUGUAUUAAUUCAUUAAAAAACACCACCCCCUCCCUGAAAUAAACUAAAAAGUAAUGAAUUCAUAGAAAAAAAUUUCACCAAGAUUGAAACUAGAGAAUAUACCUAGACUUGCACUUUGAGCUUUGAGAAAUGUGUACCUAUUCACCAUUCCAACGUGAAGAAGCUCUGCAGUAGGAAAAAUAAUUAACACACUUAUAGUCUACUGCCCAUGUAAGGAUCAGCUCCGGCUAAGAGGCCAAAGAUGGGUGACAUCGUUAUGCUCUGCCUUUAUUUUUUCUUUCUUACCCACUUAGCUUCCUAAUUGGAGGAAGGAGGCGUGGUAAAGGUAUAUGAAGACUAUGGUUUAAUUAGACCAGAAAACACUGUCAUAAUCUCUGGGGUCAUCAGAAUGUCCAGUUUUGUCUUUGGGCCAAGAUAAGGGCAGUGGGAUUUAUGAUGUGUUGUUUAUAGUCUGAAACUACUCUGGUGAUCACCAGGGUCAGUUUCUUUAAUGAUGGUUUCCAACUGGCCUAAUACAUUAAGUAAGACUGGCUGAUAACAUGACCAGACAGACAUAAAGACCCUGUUGGGAAUGACAUUGAACUCUCAAAGUCAAGAUUUCUUACACAAAUCUAUCAGCUGGAGAAAAUGAAGGCAGUGUGGUAUAUGUGUGCAAAUAAGGACAUUAUGAAGCUUAAAUAUGGAAUGUCUCUUGGACCCCCGAUGUCAUCUGUAUUCUCUUUUUCUUCUUGUACUAUAUCCUUUGCCUGUAAAUAAAAGGUUUAUUUGA